AUAGCUCUCGCUGCCACCGCUGCUGCCACUAUCGCUGUCACUGUCGCUGCUGCCUCUGUCCAGCUGAAAUGACCGUGGGGAGGCCUGAGGGAGCCCCCGGAGGCGCGGAGGGGAGCCGUCAGAUAUUUCCCCCCGAGUCCUUCGCAGACACAGAGGCAGGAGAGGAGCUGUCCGGGGAUGGGCUGGUUUUGCCCAGGGCCAGCAAACUUGACGAGUUCCUCAGCCCAGAGGAGGAGAUAGAUUCUACUUCUGACUCAACUGGGAGCAUUUACCAGAACUUACAGGAACUGAAGCAGAAAGGGAGAUGGUGUCUGUUGGAGUCUCUCUUUCAGUCUGACCCAGAGAGUGAUGAAAACCUCUCUGAAGAUGAGGAGGACCUGGAGAGUUUCUUCCAAGACAAGGACAGGGGGAUGGUGCAGGUCCAGUGCCCGCAGGCUCUGAGGUGUGGCUCCACAAGGCGCUGCAGCUCCCUGAACAACCUUCCCUCCAACAUUCCCAGGCCUCAGACCCAGCCACCCUCAGGCUCCCGGCCUCCCUCCCAGCACAGAAGCGUCAGCUCCUGGGCAUCAUCCAUUACUGUCCCUCGGCCAUUCCGCAUGACGCUGCGCGAGGCCCGGAAGAAGGCCGAGUGGCUGGGCUCACCUGCCUCCUUUGAGCAGGAGAGGCAGCGGGCCCAGAGGCAGGGUGAGGAAGAGGCCGAGUGCCACAGGCAGUUCCGGGCACAGCCUGUGCCUGCACAUGUCUACCUGCCCCUCUACCAAGAGAUCAUGGAGCGCAGCGAGGCCCGAAGGCAGGCAGGGAUCCAGAAGAGGAAGGAACUGCUCCUCUCUUCUUUGAAGCCCUUCAGCUUCCUGGAGAAGGAGGAGCAGCUAAAGGAAGCUGCUCGACAGAGAGACUUGGCAGCCACAGCUGAAGCCAAGAUCUCCAAGCAGAAGGCCACCAGAAGGAUUCCCAAGUCCAUUCUGGAGCCAGCCCUUGGGGAUAAACUCCAGGAAGCUGAGCUCUUCAGGAAAAUUCGCAUCCAAAUGAGAGCCCUGGACAUGCUCCAGAUGGCCUCUUCCCCUAUCGCCUCCUCUAGUAACCGGGCUAACCCACAGCCCCGCACAGCCACCCGAACCCAGCAGGAAAAGCUUGGGUUUCUGCACACUAACUUCAGAUUCCAGCCUCGGGUGAAUCCUGUGGUCCCUGACUAUGAGGGCCUUUACAAGGCCUUCCAGAGAAGAGCAGCCAAAAGAAGAGAAACCCAAGAGGCCACUCGCAACAAGCCCUUCUUGCUGAGGACCGCCAACCUGCGCCACCCUCAGCGGCCCUGUGAUGCUGCCACCACCGGAAGGAGGCAGGAUUCCCCACAGCCACCAGCUACACCCCUGCCAAGGAGUCGUUCUCUGAGCGGCCUUGCUUCCCUCUCUGCCAACACUCUCCCUGUGCACAUCACAGAUGCCACCAGGAAGAGGGAAUCUGCAGUCAGAAGUGCACUUGAAAAAAAGAACAAAGCAGAUGAGAGUAUUCAGUGGCUGGAGAUACACAAAAAGAAGUCUCAAGCAAUGUCCAAAUCUGUGACCUUGCGUGCAAAAGCCAUGGAUCCCCAUAAAAGCCUGGAGGAAGUGUUCAAAGCAAAGCUGAAAGAGAACCGGAACAAUGACCGUAAAAGAGCGAAAGAAUAUAAGAAAGAACUGGAGGAAAUGAAGCAGCGAAUACAAACAAGGCCCUAUCUCUUUGAACAAGUUGCCAAGGAUCUAGCCAAGAAAGAAGCAGAACAGUGGUAUCUAGACACCCUGAAGCAGGCUGGGCUGGAGGAAGACUUUGUGAGAAACAAGGGUCAAGGCACCCGGGCUGUUCAAGAGAAAGAGACCAAAAUCAAGGAUUUUCCCAGGUUCCAAGAAACUACAAAACUCAGCAUCAGAGAUCCAGAGCAGGGUUUAGAAGGAUCUCUAGAACAGCCUGCAAGCCCCAGGAAAGUACUGGAGGAGCUGUCUCAUCAGUCACCAGAAAAUCUCGUAUCACUUGCUUAAUCACUACACUUAAAAUUACUGCUUUUGAAAAAUAUUAAGCAGCUAACUUGGGUUUGAGUCAAGGCAGGGAAAACUUGGGUUUUGAGUCAUGGCUACUGUUAGAGGAUGGACAAAUGAAGAGUAGCAGAUUAACAGGCCAGGCGCAGUGGCUCACGCCUGUAAUCCCAACACUUUGGGAGGCUGAGGCAGGCAGAUCAUCUGAGGUCAGGAGUUUGAGACCAGUCCAGCCAACACGGCAAAACUCCACCUCUACUAAAAAUACAAAAAUUAGCUGGGCGUGAUGACACGUGCCUGUAAUCCUAGCUACUUGGGAAGCUGAGGCAGGAGAAUCACUUGAACCCAAGAGGCAGAGGUUGUAAUGAGCUGAGAUCACUCCACAGCACUCCAGCCUGGGCAGCAGAGCAAAACUCUGUCUGAGAAAAAAAAAGAGCAGCAGAUAACAGAGAAUAGUUCAAGGAAAUCAAAGUGGGGAGGCUCAGGUGGAGGGAUGGUAGCCUAAAGUUAAGGGUUCCUGCUUUGUGCCUCACACUUAGAGAAUUAGGUACAGAAAAGAGAGCACAGGCCCAAAUGCCUAUAAGGGGCUAGUGCAGAAACAUAAAUGCGUCCAUGGAGUGGGUGUAGACAGUAGGAGAUAGUAGACACUGGAAAGUAUCAAAUCCUGCUGGAAUAUAGGCUCAGAGUUACUACAUCAACUACAUUUUCAUCAAGCCAGAAAUUUGUAUGCUAUCAACUAAUUUAAAAAUUACUUAGAAAUAUUGUAUGGGCAAAAUAAAAUACAUCUGCAUAUCAGAUCUAGCCCAUGGGGGAUGAAAAACUUACAACUUCUAGUACAGGAUUUCUUAUCCUCAGUGCUAUUAAUAUUUUGGGCCACCUAAUUCUUUGUUGAGGGUUGGGGAAGGGAACUGUCCUGUACAUUGUAGAAUGUUUAGUAGCAUCCCUGGCCACUACCUGCUAGAUGCCAGUAGUACCCCUCUCCCCAGCUGUGACAACCAAAAAUGUCUCCAGAUAUUGCAUAUCCCCAGGGGGCAAAAAUGUGCCUGGCUGAGAACCACUGCUCUAAUAUAAAUGGCUGCAUGAAGCAAAAACUGGCAUUCUAAGAAUACAAGUAAUUGCCAUGAACACAGUCUAUGUACUAUGUGAUUAUGCAUGUCAUUAACAAAUUAAGAAUUUAAAACAAUUCUCUCCCGUUAUCUGUUUAGAAUGUGCCUGUGUGUUUAUGUGAGCAUGAGGUUCAUUUUAAGUAAACUUAAAAUUUCCCAGACAACCAAGAUUUUCUACUAGUAGGUGAACUUUGGAAUAAUUUUCUUCUCACCAAUAAUAAUUGGAUAUUCUGGCUCGGUGCAGUGGUUCAUGCUUGUAAUCCCAGCACUUUGAGGGGCCAAGGCAGGAGGAUCGCUUGAAGCCAGGCGUUCAAGACCAGCCUGGGCAACACAGACCUCAUUUCUACCAAAAAAACCACAAAAAGUUAGCUGGACUGGUGGUACAUGCCUAUAGUCCUAGCUAUUCAGGAGGCUGAGGUGGGAGGAUGCCUUGAGCGUAGGAGUUCAAGGUUACAUUGAGCUAUGAUUACACUACUGCACUCCAGCCUGGGUGACAGAGCAAGACCCCAUCUCAAAUCAUAAUGAUGAUGAGUGGAUAUUUUCUCAGUAGCUGUGGAGACAGGAUGACUGAUAGCAAGAGUGCCUGCUCUAACUAAAGCACCUUUCUCAAGCUUUUUUAAAAAAACUAUCUUUGUGGAAAAAUUCAGAAGUAUCUGUUUUUAUUGCCAUUUUCUCAGAUGCGUCUUUUUUGGUGGUGACAGAGUAACUAUCACCUGGGCUUAAGAAAUGAAGAUGUUCUUGUUGUUUCCUAAGACUCCUCGGUUCAGUUUUACUGGUAUGGAAUCCUAAGGGUAAAUCAAUACACUAUUUUAAAGGGAAAGAUUAAAUUCUUAAUCUCUAAGAAAACAAAUUUUGUAUAAAACAAGAGCCAAAGAACUGA